AUGUUUAAAAUAAAUAGUACAUACUUAUGGGGUGCCUAUGAUAUUUUGAUACAUGCAUACAAUGUAUAAUUAUCAAAUCAGGAUAUUUAGGAUAUCCAUUACCUCAAACAUUUAUCAUUUCUUUGUGUUGGAAACAUUUCAGAUCUAUUGUUUUUUAUCAUCUUCAUCAUCAUCAUUAGAAUCUAUGGUAGUAAUUUUUUCUCCACGUCUCGGUACCAGGAAAAGCUGUUUCCUUUGACCAGCUGGUUCACUUGUAUUACGUGGUCAUCAUGACUUGUAACUGAUUGUUAUUUCUCUCUUAGGAAGGGAACUCAAAGUCAAAUGUGUGUUCCUUCUCUUAUAACUGUAUAGGACCUUGUAGCAUAUGGUUUGUGUGGUAAACUUACCUCUGACUUUAUCUUAUUUUCCUUUUCAUUUUCUCUAUGCCCAAUUUCUUCUUUCUUUUUAAUUCUAAUACACCCUGUGAACGGUCUCAAAUCCUUUUUGAAGUAAUAUGGAAACAAACAAGUAAUUUCAUUAUAGCAUGUGCUCAUAUUGAAAUUUCAGAUUAAUUUUCAUUUAAUUUACCUUAAGCUAGCUACUUCCUCAUGACAAGGAGGAGCUAUAAUUUUUAUUAAGAUAUCUCAAAUCAUAUCAUAGUUGGGUUACUUCUGGGAAGGUUCCAUUUGACAGCUAAUCCUAUUGAUGGUGUUAGCUUUCUUUUAAGCUUUAAUUAAAAAGAAAAUUGUGAAAAUUUCAUUUCAUAGUUAUGACUUUUAUUCUCAUUUUUUUCUUUGACUUUUGCUCCAGCCAUCUCUCGUGGAUUUGGGAAGGAAAAGGGGGGCUUAUUUAAAAAACUUGUGAACCUAUAGUCUUAAGAAUAGUCUUCAGAAUAAGACUUUUAUAUUAGGUUAUAGCAUAGGCAGAGUAAAGUCUAUAUAUGUUGUUGUUGCCUUUCUUUUACAAACCAGAACAUUCAUUAAUUUAUUUGCAAUGACAAAAAAAAAGGAAUGUCCCAAAGUCUAGAAUAUUCCUGAAUAUUCUGGUUAUGUCAUUAGCAUAAUCACUUCCCCAAGCAGAUGUACAUGGGGCUGAUACUGUCUUUUUUGGGGGGAGAAUUCAAAAAAAUUUUAAUGAAUGAAAUGUCUCAAGUCUUUUUUAAAAUUUGUAGAUUCCCUCUUCCCCCCAUCCCCUUUUUUUUCUUUGUAAUUUAUCUUUUGAAGAACCUGUGUGGUUGUCCUGUAGAAUUUCCUACAGUCUGGAUUGCAGUUUGGUUAAACAUGUUGCUCUGCCCUCUCUAUAUCCUGUAAAUUGACAGUUUGAUGUAGAAGCUUGAUUAAGAUGUUAUUUUUUUGGUGGGGGGAGGACAAGACAACUUUAUAGAUAGUAUUGUGAGACACACAAAAUCUCUGGUUAUCUUUUGUGAUGUUAGCAGUUGUUGGUAUCACUAUUGGCUUUUGCUUCUUAAAAUCCUAAAGUGAUCACCAUGUUGUCUAGAAGAAAAUGGGGAGGCAUUGUCUGGAAAUGAUAGAGUCUGCUUUGUACAAAUAGGACUCCUGGUGUGACCACUUGAGAAUGAAGCAAUAUUGUGUGGAAUCAAGAAGAUCUAGGUAUCAGUCUUGGCUCCUCUGUGUAGGAGCUGUUUGAUCUUGCGUAAUCAACAAAAUCAGCAACAAUGACAGCAGCAGCUACAUUCACUUAGUGCUUGUUUUGUACCAGAUUAUGUGCUAAGUGCUUUAUAUACAUUGUGUAAUCUAAUCUUUAUAACAAUCCUGUAAGCCAGACAUUAUCAUAUUUAUUUUUGCAGUUCAGAAAUAUUAAAGUGUCCAAGGCCACAUUGCUAAGAAAUAGUGAAACAGGGAGUUCAAGCCCUUGCUUGACUCCAGUCUUGUGCUCAUAAUCACUUUGUUCUUCUAUAUCUGUAAAAGUGGGUAUACAAAUAGCUGCCUUAUCUACUUUGGGGGUCAAUUAGAUGUUGUUUGUGAAAAUGCCUUGAAAAAUAAGAUAGAUAUUAAAGUGAGAAGUACGCUGGGAUGACCAUUCAUGAGGAAAGGUGGAUGGUGGAGGCUUUGCCUAUAACUAAGUGACAGUGAAAAGUUUGGAUGGAAAGAACCCUGUGGUCAUUUUCUGACUUUCAUUUCUAUUACUAUUGCUGUUGAAAUGUGGAAGUGUUUUCUUCUCUUGUUAAAAUUGAGAGUGAUAGAGAUUUUACAGGUGGUAAAUGUUGCAUGUCAGAGGUUGCUUGAGAGUCCCUGGGUGAACAAUGAUGUCUUGGUUUUACUCCAUUUGCCAUAUAUGUAGGCUUAGUACAGAUGGGUUUAACAGAGAGAAAGAGUAUAGUCACAGUUCAGAUUCUUUUUUCUAAAAGGACAAAUAUUUGUUAAAAGUAGGAGAAAUUAUAAUUGAAUGUAUAAUAUUUUAUCUCUUUAGCUGGGUAGUGGGUAUAUAAUGUAUAUUAAAAUUAUUUUCAGUACCUCUUUAUUUGUCUGAACUAUUUUAUAAUGAAUAAAACUAUUAAAGUACUUACCACUAAUAUUUGCAUGUGUGACAGACUAAGAAAGAAAUAGGAGUGAGGUUGGUACCUUUAGGUCUGCCUGCCUGGGGCAGAGUGUAGGACUGUGCACUUUUUUUGAGACGGAGUUUCACUCUUGUCACCCAGGCUGGAGUGCAAUGGCAUGAUCUUGGCUCACUGCAACCUACGCCACCCGGGUUCAAGUGAUUCUCCUGCCUCAGCCUCCCCAGUAGCUGGGAUUACAGGCAUCUGCCACCACACCCAGUUAAGUUUUUGUAAUUUUAGUAGAGAUGGGGUUUCACCAUGUUGGCCAGGCAGAUCUCAAACUCCUGACUUUAAGUGAUCCGCCUUGGCCUCCCAAAGUGCUGGGAUUACAGGUGUGAGCCACCACGCCCGGCUGCACUUUUUUUCUUAAAGGAGACGGGGUCUUGCUCUGUUGCCCAGAUGGGAGUGAAGUGGCAUGAUCAUAGCUGACUGCAGCCUCAAACUCCUGGGCUCAAGUGACCCAUCUUGGCCUCCCAAGUAACUGGGACUACAGGCAUGCACUACCUGGCCUAGCUAAUUUUUAAAUUUUUUGUUAAGAUGGGUUCUCCCUGUGUUGCCCAGGCUGGUUUUGAACUCCUGGCUUCAAGUGAUCCUCCUGCCUCAGCCUCUUCGUAAUCCCAGACUGUUGGGAUUACAGGCGUGAGCCACUGUCUCUGGUAGUGCACUAUAUUUUCGGUAAACUUUGGUAAUGCGUUUAUCAGAAAGCCUUAGGGCUUGACCUGGACACAUUUUCUUGGUACUUUGCUUCUUGCAGUUCUUUUUGUACUCUGGGGACUUUAUUGCCAUAUUCUCUUUACUGUGGUGAAAUAUCUAGUAUUUCAUUCUGGUAUUCCCAACAAAGUUUUCCCAUUUUCUUGAGAUAUAAAUCAUAUUCCAUAAGUCACCCUGUUAAAGUGUACAAUUUGGCAGCUUUUAGUAUAUUCACAAAGUUGUACAACCAUCACCAUUGUGUAAUAUCAAACUUUUGUUUCCUCAGAAAGAAAUUCCGUGCCUGUUAGCAGUGUCUCCCCAUUCCUCCCUUCCUCAGCCACAGGCACCCACUAAUCUAUUUGCUGUCUCUAUGGAUUUGCCUAUUUUGUACAUUUCAUUUUAUUCCUAAAGAAUAGAGUCAUUCAUUCAGCAAGCAUUUAGAAGUCUACAGUGUUCAAGCUUUGUGUGCCAGCCUCAUAAAAAUGAAGAAAAUAUGGACCUUGCCCUCAAGGAACUCUCCAACUAUAGUAGAGGAGCAGAGGUUUAAUAGGCAAGAGAAAGAGAAAGGAAAACAGCUCUCUCUCUAAUGAGAGAGAGGGGACUUCGGAGAGGAAAAGAGGACAGGAGAUACGGCAAUCGUGGAUAGGAAAGGAGGAAAUUACGAUAGAAAAGUUGGAGAUCCUUUUGCUAACACCCCUUUGGGCAGUUGGAUGCUGAGUUCCAGGAUACACGUGCCAGAUCUGCAGGUUUGUUACACAGAUCUAUCCAUACUAAUGGAAAUGUAACUGGAACUGACUCUGAUGAUAAAAUCAAGGACCAUCAAGCAAGAUCAUGCAGUAGGCAACUUUGCUUCCAAAAGAAGUUACCAACAUUUAGAAUUUCUACUUAUUCUGAGUUGUUUAUAUAAUUGGCCUUAAAUGAGGUGAGAGUGAAGAGACUAGAGCCAUCUCUGGAAAACAUCAUUAUCCCAUUCCCCGGGAAGCUACCCUCUGGAACUCAAGAUUUGACCAUAUCUGUUUUGAGGAUUCAUUAUGAACAAAGAAGUCUCCCAGGUGUGAAGUUUUUCAACAUGAGUGGCCUCGGGGACAGUUCAUCCGACCCUGCUAACCCAGACUCACAUAAGAGGAAAGGAUCGCCAUGUGACACACUGGCAUCAAGCACGGAAAAGAGGCGCAGGGAGCAAGAAAAUAAAUAUUUAGAAGAACUAGCUGAGUUACUGUCUGCCAACAUUAGUGACAUUGACAGCUUGAGUGUAAAACCAGACAAAUGCAAGAUUUUGAAGAAAACAGUCGAUCAGAUACAGCUAAUGAAGAGAAUGGAACAAGAGAAAUCAACAACUGAUGACGAUGUACAGAAAUCAGACAUCUCAUCAAGUAGUCAAGGAGUGAUAGAAAAGGAAUCCUUGGGACCUCUUCUUUUGGAGGCUUUGGAUGGAUUUUUCUUUGUUGUGAACUGUGAAGGGAGAAUUGUAUUUGUGUCAGAGAAUGUAACCAGCUACUUAGGUUACAAUCAGGAGGAAUUAAUGAAUACGAGCGUCUACAGCAUACUGCACGUGGGGGAUCAUGCAGAAUUUGUGAAGAAUCUGCUACCAAAAUCACUAGUAAAUGGAGUUCCUUGGCCUCAAGAGGCAACACGACGAAAUAGCCAUACCUUUAACUGCAGGAUGCUAAUUCACCCUCCAGAUGAGCCAGGGACCGAGAACCAAGAAGCUUGCCAGCGUUAUGAAGUAAUGCAGUGUUUCACUGUGUCACAGCCAAAAUCAAUUCAAGAGGAUGGAGAAGAUUUCCAGUCAUGUCUGAUUUGUAUUGCACGGCGAUUACCUCGGCCUCCAGCUAUUACGGGUGUAGAAUCCUUUAUGACCAAGCAAGAUACUACAGGUAAAAUCAUCUCUAUUGAUACUAGUUCCCUGAGAGCUGCUGGCAGAACUGGUUGGGAAGAUUUAGUGAGGAAGUGCAUUUAUGCUUUUUUCCAACCUCAGGGCAGAGAACCAUCUUAUGCCAGACAGCUGUUCCAAGAAGUGAUGACUCGUGGCACUGCCUCCAGCCCCUCCUAUAGAUUCAUAUUGAAUGAUGGGACAAUGCUUAGCGCCCACACCAAGUGUAAACUUUGCUACCCUCAAAGUCCAGACAUGCAACCUUUCAUCAUGGGAAUUCAUAUCAUCGACAGGGAGCACAGUGGGCUUUCUCCUCAAGAUGACACUAAUUCUGGAAUGUCAAUUCCCCGAGUAAAUCCCUCGGUCAAUCCUAGUAUCUCUCCAGCUCAUGGUGUGGCUCGUUCAUCCACAUUGCCACCAUCCAACAGCAACAUGGUAUCCACCAGAAUAAACCGCCAGCAGAGCUCAGACCUUCAUAGCAGCAGUCAUAGUAAUUCUAGCAACAGCCAAGGAAGUUUCGGAUGCUCACCCGGAAGUCAGAUUGUAGCCAAUGUUGCCUUAAACCAAGGACAGGCCAGUUCACAGAGCAGUAAUCCCUCUUUAAACCUCAAUAAUUCUCCUAUGGAAGGUACAGGAAUAUCCCUAGCACAGUUCAUGUCUCCAAGGAGACAGGUUACUUCUGGAUUGGCAACAAGGCCCAGGAUGCCAAACAAUUCCUUUCCUCCUAAUAUUUCGACAUUAAGCUCUCCCGUUGGCAUGACAAGUAGUGCCUGUAAUAAUAAUAACCGAUCUUAUUCAAACAUCCCAGUAACAUCUUUACAGGGUAUGAAUGAAGGACCCAAUAACUCCGUUGGCUUCUCUGCCAGUUCUCCAGUCCUCAGGCAGAUGAGCUCACAGAAUUCACCUAGCAGAUUAAAUAUACAACCAGCAAAAGCUGAGUCCAAAGAUAACAAAGAGAUUGCCUCAAUUUUAAAUGAAAUGAUUCAAUCUGACAACAGCUCUAGUGAUGGCAAACCUCUGGAUUCAGGGCUUCUGCAUAACAAUGACAGACUUUCAGAUGGAGACAGUAAAUACUCUCAAACCAGUCACAAACUAGUGCAGCUUUUGACAACAACUGCCGAACAGCAGUUACGGCAUGCUGAUAUAGACACAAGCUGCAAAGAUGUCCUGUCUUGCACAGGCACUUCCAACUCUGCCUCUGCUAACUCUUCAGGAGGUUCUUGUCCCUCUUCUCAUAGCUCAUUGACAGAACGGCAUAAAAUUCUACACCGGCUCUUACAGGAGGGUAGCCCCUCAGAUAUCACCACUUUGUCUGUCGAGCCUGAUAAAAAGGACAGUGCAUCUACUUCUGUGUCAGUGACUGGACAGGUACAAGGAAACUCCAGUAUAAAACUAGAACUGGAUGCUUCAAAGAAAAAAGAAUCAAAAGACCAUCAGCUCCUACGCUAUCUUUUAGAUAAAGAUGAGAAAGAUUUAAGAUCAACUCCAAACCUGAGCCUGGAUGAUGUAAAGGUGAAAGUGGAAAAGAAAGAACAGAUGGAUCCAUGUAAUACAAACCCAACCCCAAUGACCAAACCCACUCCUGAGGAAAUAAAACUGGAGGCCCAGAGCCAGUUUACAGCUGACCUUGACCAGUUUGAUCAGUUACUGCCCACGCUGGAGAAGGCAGCACAGUUGCCAGGCUUAUGUGAGACAGACAGGAUGGAUGGUGCGGUCACCAGUGUAACCAUCAAAUCGGAGAUCCUGCCAGCUUCACUUCAGUCCGCCACUGCCAGACCCACUUCCAGGCUAAAUAGAUUACCUGAGCUGGAAUUGGAAGCAAUUGAUAACCAAUUUGGACAACCAGGAACAGGCGAUCAGAUUCCAUGGACAAAUAAUACAGUGACAGCUAUAAAUCAGAGUAAAUCAGAAGACCAGUGUAUUAGCUCACAAUUAGAUGAGCUUCUCUGUCCACCCACAACAGUAGAAGGGAGAAAUGAUGAGAAGGCUCUUCUUGAACAGCUGGUAUCCUUCCUUAGUGGCAAAGAUGAAACUGAGCUAGCUGAACUAGACAGAGCUCUGGGAAUUGACAAACUUGUUCAGGGGGGUGGAUUAGAUGUAUUAUCAGAGAGAUUUCCACCACAACAAGCAACGCCACCUUUGAUCAUGGAAGAAAGACCCAACCUUUAUUCCCAGCCUUACUCUUCUCCUUCUCCUACUGCCAAUCUCCCUAGCCCUUUCCAAGGCAUGGUCAGGCAAAAACCUUCACUGGGGACGAUGCCUGUUCAAGUAACACCUCCCCGAGGUGCUUUUUCACCUGGCAUGGGCAUGCAGCCCAGGCAAACUCUAAACAGACCUCCGGCUGCACCUAACCAGCUUCGACUUCAACUACAGCAGCGAUUACAGGGACAACAGCAGUUGAUACACCAAAAUCGGCAAGCUAUCUUAAACCAGUUUGCAGCAACUGCUCCUGUUGGCAUCAAUAUGAGAUCAGGCAUGCAACAGCAAAUUACACCUCAGCCACCCCUGAAUGCUCAAAUGUUGGCACAACGUCAGCGGGAACUGUACAGUCAACAGCACCGACAGAGGCAGCUAAUACAGCAGCAAAGAGCCAUGCUUAUGAGGCAGCAAAGCUUUGGGAACAACCUCCCUCCCUCAUCUGGACUACCAGUUCAAAUGGGGAACCCCCGUCUUCCUCAGGGUGCUCCACAGCAAUUCCCCUAUCCACCAAACUAUGGUACAAAUCCAGGAACCCCACCUGCUUCUACCAGCCCGUUUUCACAACUAGCAGCAAAUCCUGAAGCAUCCUUGGCCAACCGCAACAGCAUGGUGAGCAGAGGCAUGACAGGAAACAUAGGAGGACAGUUUGGCACUGGAAUCAAUCCUCAGAUGCAGCAGAAUGUCUUCCAGUAUCCAGGAGCAGGAAUGGUUCCCCAAGGUGAGGCCAACUUUGCUCCAUCUCUAAGCCCUGGGAGCUCCAUGGUGCCGAUGCCAAUCCCUCCUCCUCAGAGUUCUCUUCUCCAGCAAACUCCACCUGCCUCCGGGUAUCAGUCACCAGACAUGAAGGCCUGGCAGCAAGGAGCGAUAGGAAACAACAAUGUGUUCAGUCAAGCUGUCCAGAACCAGCCCACGCCUGCACAGCCAGGAGUAUACAACAACAUGAGCAUCACCGUUUCCAUGGCAGGUGGAAAUACGAAUGUUCAGAACAUGAACCCAAUGAUGGCCCAGAUGCAGAUGAGCUCUUUGCAGAUGCCAGGAAUGAACACUGUGUGCCCUGAGCAGAUAAAUGAUCCCGCACUGAGACACACAGGCCUCUACUGCAACCAGCUCUCAUCCACUGACCUUCUCAAAACAGAAGCAGAUGGAACCCAGCAGGUGCAACAGGUUCAGGUGUUUGCUGACGUCCAGUGUACAGUGAAUCUGGUAGGCGGGGACCCUUACCUGAACCAGCCUGGUCCACUGGGAACUCAAAAGCCCACGUCAGGACCACAGACCCCCCAGGCCCAGCAGAAGAGCCUCCUUCAGCAGCUACUGACUGAAUAACCACUUUUAAAGGAAUGUGAAAUUUAAAUAAUAGACAUACAGAGAUAUACAAAUAUAUUAUAUAUUUUUCUGAGAUUUUUGAUAUCUCAAUCUGCAGCCAUUCUUCAGGUCGUAGCAUUUGGAGCAAAAAAAAAAAAAAAAAAAAAAAAAGGAGUUUGCUUUUGUCGGGAGAUUGAAAGAUGUUUUUGUUUCUUUCUUUGUAAAGGCCUUGGAUAUUGAAAAAAUACCAAGGCAGAACAGUUGGACAAUCUAUUUCUUGAGCCAAAUUUAAUUAUUCUUAUUUUUGUAAUCAGUCAUUGGCUUCUUAUCUGGAUGAAGGCUUUUGGAGGAGAACCAAAACGACAAGUUCCAAGAAGAAGAUGAAGCUCCGCCUCCGCCGCUUAGUCCCAACCCUGCCCAGGAAGAAGGGCCCGUGGGGCUUUGCCUGUGCCCGUCCACCAAAGGCUGUCAUGUGUCUCGAAAUCAGCAGCCCUCCCCAUCCCAAUCCCAGGCAGCUUGUGUGUACAAUCAGCUUCUCUAGCAACUCUGUAUCUGUUGGCUUCAAGAGAAUAUUUUGCCUCCACAUAUGUACCCCUUCUCCUUUUUUUAAAGAUGGAUUUAAACCAAGAUGCCUCCAGGAAAGAGGACGAAAUGAGUAUAUUCACAGAGGAAUCCAAAAAAUACAGUUUGGGGGAAAAUGCAAUAAUUUUUGAUGAGAUGGGUGAAGGACAAGAAGUGAGUUGUGUCAAUUAUUGUAGAUACAAUUUUCUGAUUAAAUCUGGAAAAAUAAAAGGCAGCCUGUUUUUUCUGCUUUUAUUGUAUUAACAGCUGAGGUAGCUAAAGUUAUUUAAAAUAAAAUUAAAUUUAUGAUCCAAGUAGCUUAUUUUUCCCUUUAAAUCUCAUUGUAAAUAUAUUUGAUUUCUUGUAGAAAUUGAUUUCCUUCUGUUUAAUUUUAUGCUUUUAUUAUACUCUUGAUUUUUCUAAAUUUGUGUGUGAAAUAUAACAUUGAUUGAAUUGCAGUUACAUUUGGUUAGUAAUAUUUCAUUAUUUUAAUAACUGUGAUGUCAUGUAUGGAUUUACUUUGGGGUUCAAAUCAAAAUGUCACUGCCAGAAAGAGCUGUUCCAGCUGAUCUAGAGCAUACUGCCCUAGAGUGUCCCUGGGAUCAUCUGAACAGAAGUGCACAGGCUACUUGUACAGAGAAAAAAUUAAUACUCAAAGGAAAUCUUCAUUUUUUAGAUUGACUUUGGGAAUUUGAAUUUUCAUCAGUGCAAAUAUAAAUUUCUCUAUCCUGCUCUGAGGCUAAUUGGUACCAUAUUUUCCCUUUGUGUCUUGUGACUCUGCCACAUCCCAUCUCAUCCUGGCCUCUGAGUCAAGAACCCAGUGAACUGACUUUCUAGUUCUAGAAGUUCCGCUGCAAGGCCAGGAAAGCUUGAGAAAGGUAUUGUGGAAGAAGCAAAGGUAGACCCCCAUCACUCACCUUUGUCUGCAUCCCUGGGCCUGUGAAUGAUGACAGCACCUGACAUUCUGCACCAGCUACCUCUGCCUCCAUGGCAGAGAAAAGGCCAUAAGAACAGUGGAAGAGGAGCAUGGACUCAGACUUCAAGGAAGAAGCCAUUUCCCCAGGUCCUUCCUUCUGCAUCUCACCACCCCUAGUUACAAAUAACUCCAUUGAACAGCAUCUAUUCAGAAACUAUGCCGAAUAAAAAGAUUGGUGGAAGGGCUCAUGUGGUUAGCAACUAUGAAACAGAAAUAGGACACUCAGUUACAAACAUUAUCUCCUUUAGUUUUUCAGAAAAUGCAUCCCUGAUUUCAUUCAUUUCCAGCUUGAAAGCCAGCCAUAUUACUCUAGUCCCUACCAAACUGCUCUAGAAGGUCAUUUCCAUUUUGUUUGUGAUAUUUAGACGCGCAGACUUCAGGAAGUUCACCUUUAACUUCAGCAUUCCAGAUGAAGUUUCCUGACUCAGUGCUUUUGCAUAAGGAACUAGAAAAAAAAAGUAAGGAAAAUUGGAGAUGCUAACAUCCUCCCCCAUCCCAACUGCACCUUAAAAUAUGCAUGUCACCUUCAAGGUUUUAUAAUUGCACUGUUUGUUUUAUGUAUGUACAGAUUAAAAUUAUUGCUACAUUUGAGGAAAAUAAAAUUGCUUGCUUCUAUGUAAUUCCUGUCAUUCCACAGGAAAUUCACUUUUCCAGCUACUGAAUAGAAUUUGUUUAACAACCUCAUGGGUUGCCUCUUCAUUUACAGGGAAGAAAUGAAAUGUACAUCUGCAGAAAUUGCCAAAGCCCAAAUUAACGAGUAUUAUAAAAGGAUAAUAAAGCAUCCCUGAAGCCAAA